AAUAUUGCCUGGACGAUUGCUUAGAGGAGUAUUUCCUGAACUGUGUGGGUAGGUAAGUUUGAAUUUGUUAAUAUUUUCUUUGCUAAGGAGGGCUCUCAAAGGCGUAAUUAUUAUAAAGGGUAUUUGUAGACCUUGAAACAUGUAGCAAUACUUUUAGUCCAAGUAAGCCCUUUGAUUGCUUUUUAACUUCCCAUUUAGUAUUCCAAGUGGAUUCUGAACUUGGUGAAAUUAGUGGUAACCCAGUCUCCUCAGGGUCUUGCCUCCUGUCUUCUGGCUUACAGAGGUGGAGAUUCAAAGGAUUUCUUUCCUUUAGGUCAUGGUAUUUAAGAGAAUAAUUUUCCCCUCAUAUUAUAGCUAAGAAGAGGUCUGUUGACUAUUACAGAUUGGGAAUCCAUGGGCAUAAUAUACGAAAUGUUUAAAAAAUUACUUUGAACUUAACCUUAUAUGCAAAACAUUGAUUAUCUUAUAAAUAUUAACUGCUUUGGAUUGUUUACACAAUGUUAGUUGUACUAUGAAAAUUUGCUUAUUAACCAGGUUUAGACUUCUUAGGUUGUUCUUGGCUUUGAGUCCACAGAUUUAACACUGCCAAAUUUCUGUGUAAACAUUUUGCUUGGGACCUAAAAUACAGUUGAAUAUGUGUAUUUAAAGUUUUUUUUUUUAAAGCCCAUGUAUAUUAAUGGAACUUGUAAAUGUUUAAAUAGUCAAUUAAUGGAAGCUUUUAAGAAACAACUCUUUCAAAAUAUUCAAUUUUAUAAUUAUGAUGUUUUAAAUAUCAAACUUGAGUUAGUGACAAACAUGUAAUUCAUAAUAUAUAAAGAUCUAUAAGUAGUUCUUAUUGAUUUAUUACAUUUAAUCUUACUCAGAAGGAACUUUUUUGUUAUUAUUCUGUCACUAAUAAUUAAGUGCAAGGCUAUUUAAAAACAAAUAAGAGCUAAUAACAUUGUAACACAGACUAGAUAGAGAGCAAAAAUAAAUAACUGAUUAAGUUACUGUUUUGGUCUUGGGAAAUGUGGUAGGUUCUUGAGUUUAGGUGCCAUGGUUAUGGCUGUUUUGAUCCUUUUUUGAAAUACAUUCUUGGAUGUGUUGAUUUUCUUGUAAUGUCACUAUUAUUUCUUAAGACCCUUAUAUACUGUAAAGAGCAUUAUCAAUUUACACAAAUUUUAACUACCCAUAGAAAUAUUGUAUACAGCUUUUUUGUAGCAUAAAUAGGUGAAGUUCCUCAAGAUGUUUAUGGCCUGGUAUAUUCUUACCCUUGCUAUAAAGCUUUGGUCAGCUUUAGUGGCCAAACUCUAAGGCAAAUGGCAGUAUUAAUGUGGAGUGUAAAUCUCCAUAUAUGUUCUUGGAAUGGUAUGUAAAAUAUUUUGUUCCCUGAUCCACCUGUCCCCACCUUUAGUAAGAUACCCUUGUGUCUGCAGUAGCUUGAGUUAUAAAAGAGGUUUCCGUUUUUCAGCAACUAGACUUGGAAACAAAUUUUUUCAGUUUAACUUAAGCAAAUUGUAUAUAAGAGGAAAUGACUAUGGAGGAGAUACGCUGCUUAGUCUCAUUUCUAUGUAAAUAGUUCUGACAUAAAUUGUAUAGAGAAGUCUCCUUUGUAGUUUACUUUUCAGUGAUGUCAUUUGUCAUUAAAUCGUCAAGGUAGGUAUGAACCUUGGAGUUUUAAGGUGACAAAAAUGAACUCAUUACACUUUAGACUUUUGGCCAGGUUCUGUAACUUAUGCCUGUAAUCCCAGCACUUUGGGAGACUGAGGCAGGAGGAUUGCUUGAGCCCAUGAGUUCAAGGCCAGCCUGGGCAUCAUAGUGAGACCUUGUCUCUACCAAAAUAAAUAAAUAAAUAAAUAAAUAAAUAAAUAAAUAAAUAAAUAAAUAAGCCUGGCAUGGUGGUGCAUGCCUGUAGUCCCAGCUACUCAAGAGACUAAGUUAGGGAGGAUGGCUUGAUCCCAGGAGACUGAGACUGCCAUGAGCUGUGAUUGUGCCAUUGCACUCCAGCAAGGGCGACAGAGUGAGACUGUCUUAGAAAAAAUUCUAGCCUUUUAAAUAAUAGUGUAGUUGAAUUGUAUAAAUAUUUUUUGAAGAGAAUAUAAUAAGGUAGGUUAUCAUGUAGUCUUUUUGAUCAUUUAUUUAUAGGAUAUUUCUAAUGUAAACAAUCCAGUAUUUUAAAAUUUCCUUUUUUUUAGAGUUUGUUUGUGUAUUUGUUUUGACUUGUUUAAUUUGACAUGUAAGCACUUAAAAAUUGACUUUCCAGCUACAUGAAGAAAUUAUACGUCGGUUAAAUUUGUGGCAUUUUUAUACAGAAUCGUGUGUACAAAAUAUAUUAACUAGGUUUGUUAAUUUGAUUAGAAAAAACUUGUGGUAGUUUUAAUGCUCAAUAUAUUUUCUAAAAUGCAAAAGCAAUUUGUGAAAUAUUGUCUCUCUGUACUUGGUAAUGUAAGAUCUGAGCUGAAUGAAAUGUGAGUUUCUUAAGCUUGUCUUAGAUUUUGUAUCAACAUUUGUUCAAGAGCUUGGUUUUAGGAACAUUUGUGUGCAUUUUCUUGAUUAUUAAAAAUUCUUUGUGUCAUAUUUAGAUGUAAUUUAGAGCAAUAUUAUUUAACUUUGCCAAUUAUAUUAUUCUGAUCACUAGAUUUAAUGCUCUGGUAACAACUCUCUGACAACUCAUUAUUACUCUAGUAUUAGAUUCCAUUGGAUUCUUUAUCUUCCUUGUUUCUAAAAAAAUGCCUUUCCUCAUUAUGCAAGUAAUUUUUCUUUAUUUCACCAUUUAUACAGUUGGCCAGACCAAAUGACAUAGUGAGUAUCCCUUAAGCCAGGGGUCCCCCAACCCCUGGGCCAUGGUUCAGUACCGGUUGGCAGCCUUUUAGGAACUGGGCCGCACAGCAGAAGGUGAGCAGUAGGCCAGCAAGCAUCACUGCCUGAGCUCUGCCUCCUGUCAGAUCAGCAACAUCAUUAGAUUCUCAUAGGAGUCGAACCCCAUUGUGAACUGCACAUGUGAGGGAUCUAGGUUACGUGUUCCUUAUGACAAUCUAACUAAUGCCUGAUGAUCUGAGGUGGAACAGUUUCAUUCUGAUCCAUCCCGCCUACUCCUGCCUUGGAAAAAUUGUCUUCCAUGAAACCAGUCCCUGGUGCCAAAAAGGCUGGGGACCACUGCGUUAAGCAGAGCCGUGAAUAUCAAUCUUGGACACAAAGCCUGGGAUUGUGGGUGGGGAAAGCCCUCCCGUUGCUCUGGCCUGGCAUUCCAAAGACUCUUUCAAUUCUCUUAACUUAUUCAAAGCCUGGAUUCUAAAAGCCAAUUGGGCUCCCUUUGCCCAUUCAUAAUUCAUGCUACAGUCUUCUGGCUAAAAAUUGUCAGUAGAGUUUCCAUUUCCCAUUAUAUGAAAUUCAAUGUCCAGUGUGUAACUUAUCUUUUGAGUCGUGUAUCUUAAUGUAUGGCUUAAGCUUCUUCUUUAUGCUUUACAGUUUCCAUUUCCUGCCUUUUUUUCUUGACACGUGGUGUAAUUAGAAAGUCUCUCCCUCAUAUUCAAAAUUUACCUCAUCCUUAAGGUUUACUGACCACUGCCAUUAAAUUUUUCUUGGUUUCACCUUCUUUUUUCUGCAUUUUAUACCAGUGUUUUGUGUUCCAUCUUCUGUUAUAUUUAUUUUUACAUGUGUUAUAUUUUACUUCCUUUCUAAUGACUGAGUUUAACUGAUUGAAUUACUUAAAGUCUAUCUCUUACUAUGAUGGGUUAGAGGUGGUUUUGUCUUGUUUCUUCUAGGUUGCCUUGCAUUCAGUACAUGCUUAUUAUAAAUAUUUGGUUACUGAAAAAAAUGAAGUGAUAUGACAGUGUUAUUGAUUACAAGACAUUUUACUCCUUUGUUGGAAUGGACAUUUGGGGACAGGGGAUCAACUGGAAAUCUAAACAAGUGUGGCAUGGCUCUCUGAAUCAGGCUGUCCCCAGCAGGGAAAGCUGAUGAAACAAUUAAGGCUGCAGCUAAGAAAUGUUUUAAAUCAUGUUGCAUAGUGGCUCAAUACUGACAGGCAAAGGACAGCUCUUACUAGGGAAAGACUUUGGACUGAUAGGAAAUUGAAGAGAAACACAGGCUUUGUAGAUAGUGACUACAUUUCUAACUCAGAUAACAUUUUCUGUGAGUUCAUAGUGUGAGAAUAAAUACAGUCAAUUCUGCUGUAAUGAUUGUUUUGAAAAAUGGGAGUUUUUAUUCUUUCAUGAUUGAUAUUAGGCAACACUUUGAGCAUAAUGCAAAUUUCACUUUUGCUUAUGCGUGAUUUCACCUGAGAAAUAGUAGGCGUGCACAGAAAAUUUCACCCAACUAAAAUGAGCUGCCUAGGCUACACAAAGUGUACAUGCACACAUCUCAGACAUUGCCUGGCUGUCUCACUUUGCCACAUGUUAUGAGCCAUAUUCAUUCAUAUUUUGUAUUAUAAUUUCCCCUCCAAUUUCAGAUAACCCAUCUUGCACCACUUCCCAAUAAUUUACAUGCAAGGCUUGUGGCUGCCUGGAAUAGAAAUAUUUCUUUCCCACAAAUAACAAUUAUGUUAACAUUUUUGAGCCUUAACUAUGUGCUAAGCACUAUGAUAAGUGCUUAACAUGGAUUAUGUUAUGGAAUUCUCACAAAACCUGAUACAGUAGGUAUUAUUACUGUCUUUACAGAUGAGGAAAGUGAGGCUUAGAGGGGUUAAUUAACUUGCCCAUGGUCAAUAACUCAUAAAUGGCAGAGCCAAUUCUUGAAUCGAGUCUGAUUUAGAUCUUAGUGUUCUCUUACUUUGUAGAUUACAGAUAAGUAGCUUUCACUUGUGUUAUUUCAUAUGCAUUUAAUAACUGUCUCUGAUUGGCAUCAUAGGCUGUUUCGAUCCCUAUGAUAGAUGAGGAAACAACGCUACUCAGGGUAAGAAUGCACAGAUCAUCAUAGGCAGAGCAAUAACAGGAACUCAUUCUCAUACCUAAAUCAGAAUUUUUUUCCUGGGGCUUAUACAUAAAAGGGGAAGAAAACAAUUAGAGAAUUAGAGAUAGGGAGGUGAACUGAACUACAAAAAGAGGAUGAAAUGAUUGUGUUGGAAGUUGGGGAACAAAAGAAGGUGAGUUAUAAUAGUACUUCAGAAUUGUAAGGAGAGAGUCUAAUGAAAAAUGAACACUAGGGGACUUGUAACUCUGUGGUACAUAAAGCCUAAUCAAAUUCUUACAAAGGAAUUAAAACCACCAACUUCAUUACAAGAUUGUGGUAAGAGAAAUCUGAUCAUGAGCAUAAAUCACUAGUAGUAAUACGCUCAGAAAUCAGAGGGAAGAGCAAGGCGAUACCAGAGGAAGACUUCGGAAGGAUUUAUUUGUAUUUGUUUUGUAGCAUGUGAUUUUUUUUUUUUUUAAGGUAGUGAGUUACCUUACAGGCCCUUACAGAUAAGCAAGUACUUGAUUAGUGUUUGUUAUACUGAAAGCUUAAUAAAUAGUAAGGAGAGUAGUUGUUCAGUUGGGUAUUGAUUAAGGUGAAGUAAUAGGAAAAGUAAGGGUAGAAUCGAUGAGUAAUGAUGAACUCAAAGCAGAGGGUCAGCAAACUCUAGCCAUUGGGCUGUUUUCUUUCUACAAGCUGAGAAUGCUUUUUACAUUUUUGGUAGGUUAUUAAAAACAAAAAUGAAGAAUAUUGACAGAGACUGUAUGUGGCCCACAAAGCCUAAAAUAUUUAUAACCUGGCUCUUUACCGAAAGUUUGUCAACCCCUGACCUGAAAUACAUACCAUGAAGAAAAAAGUUAGACUUGUUCCCUUUUAGGAAAUUGGAUUAGGUACUGUAAAGUGUAAUAUUUCAUGGGGCUACAUUUUCAAACAUGUGCCUUUUUCCCACAUGGAGGAAAGAACUGUCAUGUAUUUAGCCUGCUCUUUUGCUAUAGGGGUUUUGCAUACUUCGAUUGUUCUUAACCUUGAGAGAUACUAUAACCACUUUACAAAUGAAGAAACUAGGCUCAUAGAGGCUAAGUAAGCCUAAAGUUUUACAUUUAAUAAGGACUGAAAUGUAAGCUUGUCUGGCUUGCUAACUAGAUAUCAAAUAUGGGCAUUUGUAUAAAUUUAGUUAGUAUGUAAAAUAGAAAAAAAACUUGUACACAUAGACAAUAGAGUAGGUUGGAGAAUUGUGUCAUUUUAUUACAAAAUUUGCCCAAGGAAGAAUAUCUUUGGAUAAGUUGUAAAAAAAAACAUAAAAUAUAAAGAACAGAAAAUUCUAGUCUCAUAUUAAAAAUGUAAUAUUCACCUAAAAGAAAGAUGAGAUUCAAGAUGUUUUUGAAAGAAAAUGCAAAAUACAAAAGUGUGUUUUGCUUCAAUAGAAAGUAUACCAGCUAGUACUUUAUUUUUGAAAUGCAGAUAUUAAGCAAAUAUUGGCCCAAAUGUCUAACAGUAAAGAUUUAUGAAGAGAAUUUCAGAGUGCUGUGAAAACAUGUAAUGUAGAAAUCUAGGAUAGAUUGGGAGUCAGGGAAUGGUUUCCCAAGAAGGGGCCAUUUAAGCUGAGAUACAAGAUUUAGAUAGGCAAAGAUAUAAAAGAUAAUUAUUCUAGACAAGUGUGAUAGGCCUCGAGGAAGGAAGAACUUGGCAUUGUCAAUGCUGCAGUGCUUCCCGCCUUGCCUUUUGAAUCCCAGGUUCCACGCAGGAAAAGGCAAGGCCAGGCUCCUCCCCUCUGCAAAGGUGCAAACUUGCUCAGGCUCCACCCCAGUGCACAGGCCGGCAGGAGCUUUGCCAGGGAUCCCCUCCCACUUAGCUGUCUCAAUGGGAGGGACCAUUUUACAAGAUGUUUACCAUACUGGUUUGCAGAAUUAGAGAGAGUAACCUUAGGUGAGGAGAAGACUGGGAUUUGGAGACAGAAGGAAAGAAAAUAGAUUCAGGGUCAUUCUUGAAUGUUAGCCUUCUUUGAGUUAAAAAAAAAAUAGCUGAUAGGUGGUAGCAGCAACACAUGUGCCUCUGAUUGUACAAGAAUUUAAUAAUGAUACUUGUGUAUGUUUUACAUAAGCUUAAACUUUAGUGAACUUUAGUUAAUGAUAUCAAACAUUGAGGGUUUUAAUGUCUUUCUACUGGAUAUCAUAAGUCUGUUUUUCCUUACGAAAAGGGUAAUAUUGGCUAGCCGUUGAGGUUAGUGUUUGCUAAGAGUUGGAAGUUUUGAACAGUGAGGAAAACAAUGUCACUGGGCUCAUUUCCAAGAGGGUAUUCUAACUAUUGCAGUCAACAACUGAUUUGCCAUAAAAUGUCAAUAACUUUUUAAAAGGAAGGUACAUUCAUGUGUUUAUUUUGCUUUUUAAAUGAGUGUUAAGUACUUUAAUUAGCAUCAUUUUAUAAUUAUUGAUAUUUUGUAUGGGAUUUAAUAAUGGAUUAGUUAAUUAUGAAAACAAGAUCUAAAUGUUUUCUUCUCCAAUUGCCGUUAAAAUUUGUUGAAAUCACCUUAUUGAACAGAUUUUUUUUAAACCCCUUGGAGUACUAGUGGGUGUUAUUUUGUUGAAUGAAUGUUUUACCCAAACUUAUAUGCAUAUUAGAUUGUUUAAAAGCUCAAUUAAAAAGUGAAAAAUAGACACUGAAAAUUUUUUGAGUGAUUUCACAUGUGUUCAUGAAACAAUAUAUCUAUUACAAAUCAUUGAAUAUUUUAAAAGUAAUGUCAUGUAUUCAUUUUCUUAUUUUAUCUCCUCAGUAGACUGAGAUCAGUGUGUAGGGGUGAAGCAAGGAGUCCUACUCUGUUUGACUAAGAACACACAAGUGAAAGACACAAUGAAUGGUCAUAUUUCUAAUCAUCCCAGUAGUUUUGGAAUGUACCCAUCUCAGAUGAAUGGCUACGGAUCAUCACCUACCUUUUCCCAGACGGACAGAGAACAUGGUUCAAAAACAAGUGCAAAGGCCCUUUAUGAACAAAGGAAGAAUUAUGCACGGGACAGUGUCAGCAGUGUGUCAGAUAUAUCUCAAUACCGUGUUGAACACUUGACUACCUUUGUCCUGGAUCGGAAAGAUGCUAUGAUCACUGUUGAUGAUGGAAUAAGGAAAUUGAAAUUGCUUGAUGCCAAGGGCAAAGUGUGGACUCAAGAUAUGAUUCUUCAAGUGGAUGACAGAGCUGUGAGCCUGAUUGAUUUAGAAUCAAAGAAUGAACUGGAGAAUUUUCCUUUAAACACAAUCCAGCACUGCCAAGCUGUGAUGCAUUCAUGCAGCUAUGAUUCAGUUCUUGCACUGGUGUGCAAAGAGCCAACCCAGAACAAGCCAGAUCUUCAUCUCUUCCAGUGUGAUGAGGUUAAGGCAAACCUAAUUAGUGAAGAUAUUGAAAGUGCAAUCAGUGACAGUAAAGGAGGGAAACAGAAGAGGCGGCCCGACGCCCUGAGGAUGAUUUCCAAUGCAGACCCUAGUAUACCGCCUCCACCCAGAGCUCCUGCCCCUGCGCCCCCUGGGACCGUCACCCAGGUGGAUGUUAGAAGUCGAGUGGCAGCCUGGUCUGCAUGGGCAGCCGACCAAGGGGACUUUGAGAAACCAAGGCAGUAUCAUGAGCAGGAAGAAACACCUGAGAUGAUGGCAGCCCGCAUUGACAGAGAUGUGCAAAUCUUAAACCACAUUUUGGAUGACAUUGAAUUUUUUAUCACAAAACUCCAAAAAGCAGCAGAAGCAUUUUCUGAGCUUUCUAAAAGGAAGAAAAACAAGAAAGGUAAAAGGAAAGGACCAGGAGAGGGUGUUUUAACGCUGCGGGCAAAACCUCCACCUCCUGAUGAAUUUCUUGACUGUUUCCAAAAGUUUAAACACGGAUUUAACCUUCUGGCCAAACUGAAGUCUCAUAUUCAGAAUCCUAGUGCUGCAGAUUUGGUUCACUUUUUGUUUACUCCAUUAAAUAUGGUGGUGCAGGCAACAGGAGGUCCUGAACUAGCCAGUUCAGUACUUAGUCCCCUAUUGAAUAAGGACACAAUUGAUUUCUUAAAUUAUACUGUCAAUGGUGAUGAACGGCAGCUGUGGAUGUCAUUGGGAGGAACUUGGAUGAAAGCCAGAGCAGAGUGGCCAAAAGAACAGUUUAUUCCACCAUAUGUUCCACGAUUCCGCAAUGGCUGGGAGCCCCCAAUGCUGAACUUUAUGGGAGCCACAAUGGAACAAGAUCUUUAUCAACUGGCAGAAUCUGUGGCAAAUGUAGCAGAACAUCAGCGCAAACAGGAAAUAAAAAGAUUAUCCACAGAGCAUUCCAGUGUAUCAGAGUAUCAUCCAGCCGAUGGCUAUGCGUUCAGUAGCAACAUUUACACAAGAGGAUCCCACCUGGACCAAGGGGAAGCUGCUGUUGCUUUUAAGCCAACUUCUAAUCGCCAUAUAGAUAGAAAUUAUGAACCACUCAAAACACAACCCAAGAAAUAUGCCAAAUCCAAGUAUGACUUUGUAGCAAGGAACAACAGUGAGCUCUCGGUUCUAAAGGAUGAUAUUUUAGAGAUACUUGAUGAUCGGAAGCAAUGGUGGAAAGUUCGAAAUGCAAGUGGAGACUCUGGAUUUGUGCCAAAUAACAUUUUGGAUAUUGUGAGACCUCCAGAAUCUGGAUUGGGGCGUGCUGAUCCACCUUAUACUCAUACUAUACAGAAACAAAGGAUGGAGUAUGGCCCAAGACCAGCUGAUACUCCCCCUGCUCCAUCACCUCCUCCAACACCAGCUCCUGUUCCUGUUCCCCUUCCCCCUUCCACUCCAGCACCUGUUCCUGUGUCAAAGGUCCCAGCAAAUAUAACACGUCAAAACAGCAGCUCCAGUGACAGUGGUGGCAGUAUCGUGCGAGACAGCCAGAGACACAAACAACUUCCGGUGGACCGAAGGAAAUCUCAGAUGGAGGAAGUGCAAGAUGAACUCAUCCACAGACUGACCAUUGGUCGGAGUGCCGCUCAGAAGAAAUUCCAUGUGCCACGGCAGAACGUGCCAGUUAUCAAUAUCACUUACGACUCCACACCAGAGGAUGUGAAGACGUGGUUACAGUCAAAGGGAUUCAACCCUGUGACUGUCAAUAGUCUUGGAGUAUUAAAUGGUGCACAACUUUUCUCUCUCAAUAAGGAUGAACUGAGGACAGUCUGCCCUGAAGGGGCGAGAGUCUAUAGCCAAAUCACUGUACAAAAAGCUGCAUUGGAGGAUAGCAGUGGCAGCUCCGAGUUACAAGAAAUUAUGAGAAGACGACAGGAAAAAAUCAGUGCUGCCGCUAGUGAUUCAGGAGUGGAAUCUUUUGAUGAAGGAAGCAGUCACUAAUUUGUUUGUUUGUAUUUAAACUCCAUUGUUUUUGGCAUUAUUCCAACAUGCUUUGUUUUAAGAAGCCUUGAAGGGAAUGUCAGAUUCAUUUUUCUUGAUGUAAUUUAUCACCAUAAAAAAAAACCCAUGCAAACCUGAGUGAGCACAGGAUUUGCUUCUAGGCCCAUUAUUUUUAUUAAAACUGAAAAAAUUUAAACUGAAUUUUUUGACCUUGGAAAAUAUUUUUCUUACUUUACCAAGGUGAAGUUUCCUUAAUUAGACUAAUUAUUUUAUCCCCAUCCCAGGGUAUAAACAGGAAUUGUUUUGAUAGUGGUGGAGUUAUUCACUGCAACAAAGCAACAAUGUUGUCCAUGAUUCAAAAUCUAAGCAGUUUCGAUUUUGCCUGUGAAUAUGGUGUCUGUCAUUCAGGGCAUAGCUCACUGUAGGCUAGCCUCUGCUUACUUAAGUCUCUUCUCUGACAUACUCAAUGGAAGAAUAUUUAGAUUUAUUUAAAGUUCUUAAUGCCAACAGUUUAAAAAAAAAUUAAAACAUUUGAAUGAACUGUAAAGUACAGCCAUACCUUGGACAUGCAAAUAUAAAUCUAUGGAGCAUUCUCAAGAGAGUUUGUCAUGGCUCUGUUGAUUGCAACUCCUUGUAUAGCUUGUAUUUUGAUUUAGUUUAUAUUCUGCUUAUUAUGUAUACUGUGUUCUUAUAUAUGAGAAAGCACAAAUGCGAAAGAGGUCAUGUCUUCUCAAAAUCUAGCAAAGGAAGUAGUCUGCAUUGGUGUGCAUUACAGUAUUUUGCUUAAUGAAAGCCUCAGUUCUGAAUGUUGAUAUGAGUAGUUAAAAGGAAGUGGGGCCAUUUUAUGUGUUUAUCUGUGUCAAGUAUUUCUGGUAAUAAGAAGCACUUAAUUUACACAUAUUUUAAUCCUGUGAAAGAUUCCACAUAGAGAAAAGAAAGAUACCUAACCUUCAACAAAUGUUAUUUUUGGAAACACAAUUUUUGUCAUUAAAUGUUAUAUUAUUUCACAUAUAUAAAACAGAUGUUAUGUAAGAAUGUUGUAUAUUUUAACAUAAAUCAUUUAGAGAAAUUAUCUAGAUUCAUUAAUUUUCAUAGUGCCUUUUUCACAUGAGUCAGCUGGAAAGUCUGCAAUAAACAGUAUUUGCUGUCUGUUAAUAAAUGGUUUCUGUCUCAUUAGCAAAAA